ACUGGAGACACUGAAGAAGGCAGGGGCCCUUAGAGUCUUGGUUGCCAAACAGAUUUGCAGAUCAAGGAGAACCCAGGAGUUUCAAAGAAGCGCUAGUAAGGUCUCUGAGAUCCUUGCACUAGCUACAUCCUCAGGGUAGGAGGAAGAUGGCUUCCAGAAGCAUGCGGCUGCUCCUAUUGCUGAGCUGCCUGGCCAAAACAGGAGUCCUGGGUGAUAUCAUCAUGAGACCCAGCUGUGCUCCUGGAUGGUUUUACCACAAGUCCAAUUGCUAUGGUUACUUCAGGAAGCUGAGGAACUGGUCUGAUGCCGAGGUAAGAAACUUGCUGCCUGCUUGGCCUGGCCUUUCUAGAGCAAAGGACCAGCCAGAGCCCCAGAUCUCAUUUGAUUCAGGAUCAAGUGUCCUUCCUGGGCACUAUGAAGAGAAGCCCCUUUGGCUGGUGAAAUGGAGAGAAGAGGGUUGUGUGUUCAACUCAUUCAAUUCUGUAAGCAUUGCUGAAGCAGGUGCUGUAUGCCAGACCCUAGAUGGGCUACAAGCACAUACGGAUACAUAGGAAAGAGCCCCUACCCUCAGCAAGCUCACUGUCAGUAAAGGAGACAGAAAUACAUCAAUCAAAGGAGGAAGAGAAGAUGAGGAAUUCACAGAAAGGAUAAUGGAGUUUCUGUACAAGAUUUACCAGAAAGAGAGUGGUGUGUAGACAUGCCUGGAGCAGACACCUUGGAGCCGCUGACAGAAGGUGAAGCAGUCCAAGAAAAUGUGGAAACUUUUCCGCUGCUCUACACAGUCCACAAACCUGUCCAUUUUAUUUCGUUGAAGCUUUGUCUGAGAGAUAACCAAAUAGACAGUCAAAGUAAGUUAUCUCAGCCACAUAUGGGGAGUGGAUGCUGCUGAAUUGUGAUUAAUUGGGGGAGCCAUAUAGGUACAUUUGGCAUGAUCUGGGCCUAUGCGGUCUUACAAUCCCUGUAUAAAACUAGACAAUGAAAAACAGAAAACAAAACAAACAAACAAAAAAACAAGAACGAAGCACCUACCACAUGCCAGCUACUGAGGCUAUGAAGGUAUUCUCCCGCCUUAGAAAGCCCAGGAUUAAUGCAGGAUUGCGACAUUUAAACAGAACAUUUCCAUACAGCAUGAGUAUAAAUGACUUUCCCAAGUUUACACUGAGAGUAACUGACACAGCAACCCCAGCAAAGUCUGAGCUGAGUCCUGAAUAAUUGUAUAAAAAGGGGAGAGAAACAGAGUGAAGAAAGGGUUUCCCAGACUCUGUCCCAGGAAAGAAAAUGAGCUCGUGGAGAGGAAUAGACUUUCUCUAUGAAAACAGAGGGAACAAAGAGGAAGAUGUCUGGGAACCGAGGAGUAAUAGAGACCUGAGUUUACAUCACUACUCUGCCACUCCCUAGGUACCUCCCUUUACCUGUUUCCCUACUGGAAAGUGGGAUAAUACUUUUUACCUCAUGGACUUGUCAGGAGGAUUCAUUAAAACGACUCGCAUAAAGCCUAUGCCACAUGGUAGAUGCCAAUUCAGGGUCUCAAGAAAGAACAGCCCACAGGAUUGACACUGAACCUUAACAAAGUUAACAGGACCAAGGUGCAGAGAGGGUGCUAGGACAGCGAAGCCAAAGAGGACCCCUCAAACCCAACAAGAGCUGUGCGGCUCCCUGAUUCCUCGCCAGUGUUGCUACCGCCCUUGGCUCUUCUUGCAUGGCUGGCUCUUGAGACCCCUGGAAGCUGAUGGAGGCAACGUGAGAAGCACAUGGACAUCCGACCUUGAGCUUGAGAGGCAGAGGCCUGAGUUCUAGUUACAGCCCCAGCAGUACCAGUUGUGUGGACUGGGAGGGAGGCUAUCACGUACAUACUUCAAGCCUCCAAACCUGUUUCCCCUUCUGACACAGGAUCUUCUGUGGCUGGUAUAGAGUGGGCACUCAAUAAAUGCUGUCUGGUCGUCUGGCUGGCAUGCCUCAUGGGCCUGAGAAUUGAAUAGAAUUACAGUGAUAGAAGCAUGCUGGUAUUGUAAGUGGUUUGUAAGUGUGAGGACUAAAUUAUUAUUAAAUAGUAAUCACAUCUAAUCUUGGAUAAAUUAGUAAAAGCAAGAAUGGGAGCAGUAAAAACCUAAGCAACCCGAACUAAAAUUUUAUUGAAUUAAUUCAAUUUCUUGUCAUGUAACACAACCCCAGAAGAGAAUAAAAUAAAGUUUAUAUACAUACACCCAUA